GCCAGACGUUCUUCGCCGAGAGUCGUCGGGGUUUCCUGCUUCAACAGUGCUUGGACGGAACCCGGCGCUCGUUCCCCACCCCGGCCGGCCGCCCAUAGCCAGCCCUCCGUCACCUCUUCACCGCACCCUCGGACUGCCCCAAGGCCCCCGCCGCCGCUCCAGCGCCGCGCAGCCACCGCCGCCGCCGCCGCCUCUCCUUAGUCGCCGCCAUGACGACCGCGUCCACCUCGCAGGUGCGCCAGAACUACCACCAGGACUCAGAGGCCGCCAUCAACCGCCAGAUCAACCUGGAGCUCUACGCCUCCUACGUUUACCUGUCCAUGUCUUACUACUUUGACCGCGAUGAUGUGGCUUUGAAGAACUUUGCCAAAUACUUUCUUCACCAAUCUCAUGAGGAGAGGGAACAUGCUGAGAAACUGAUGAAGCUGCAGAACCAACGAGGUGGCCGAAUCUUCCUUCAGGAUAUCAAGAAACCAGACUGUGAUGACUGGGAGAGCGGGCUGAAUGCAAUGGAGUGUGCAUUACAUUUGGAAAAAAAUGUGAAUCAGUCACUACUGGAACUGCACAAACUGGCCACUGACAAAAAUGACCCCCAUUUGUGUGACUUCAUUGAGACACAUUACCUGAAUGAGCAGGUGAAAGCCAUCAAAGAAUUGGGUGACCACGUGACCAACUUGCGCAAGAUGGGAGCGCCCGAAUCUGGCUUGGCGGAAUAUCUCUUUGACAAGCACACCCUGGGAGACAGUGAUAAUGAAAGCUAAGCCUCGGGCUAAUUUCCCCAUAGCCGUGGGGUGACUUCCCUGGUCACCAAGGCAGUGCAUGCAUGUUGGGGUUUCCUUUACCUUUUCUAUAAGUUGUACCAAAACAUCCACUUAAGUUCUUUGAUUUGUACCAUUCCUUCAAAUAAAGAAAUUUGGUACCCAGGUGUUGUCUUUGAGGUCUUGGGAUGAAUCAGAAAUCUAUCCAGGCUAUCUUCCAGAUUCCUUAAGUGCCGUUGUUCAGUUCUAAUCACACUAAUCAAAAAGAAACGAGUAUUUGUAUUUAUUAAACUCAUUAGUUUGGGCAGUAUACUAAGGUGUGGCUGUCUUGGAUUCAGAUAGAACUAAGGGUUCCCGACUCUGAAUCCAGAGUCUGAGUUAAAUGUUUCCAAUGGUUCAGUCUAGCUUUCACAGUUUUUAUGAAUAAAAGGCAUUAAAGGCUGAA